AGUGUGUGGGCGGCGGCGGCGGCGGCUGCGCGCUUGGGGCCCGGGGCGCGGGGCGAGGCCGUGGGGACGUGCGAGCGGGGCCGCGGUGGGGCUCGGGGGCGCGUCCACGUGGCCAGAGGGCGGCCACCCGGAGCCAGCGGAGGGACAGGCCUGUCCCCAGGCGCGGCUGCCGGCCAUGCCCUCUGUCUGCCUCCUCCUGCUGCUCUUCCUUGCCGUGGGGGGGGCCCUGGGCAACAGGCCCUUCCGUGCCUUCGUGGUGACAGACACCACGCUUACCCACCUGGCUGUGCACCGGGUGACUGGGGAGGUGUUCGUGGGCGCAGUGAACCGAGUCUUUAAGCUGGCCCCCAACCUGACUGAGCUGCGGGCCCAUGUCACGGGGCCCGUCGAGGACAACGCUCGCUGCUACCCGCCCCCCAGCAUGCGCGUGUGUGCCCACCGCCUGGCCCCCGUGGACAACAUCAACAAGCUGCUGCUCAUAGACUAUGCGGCCCGCCGCCUGGUGGCCUGCGGCAGCAUCUGGCAGGGCAUCUGCCAGUUCCUGCGUCUGGACGACCUCUUCAAGCUGGGUGAGCCGCACCACCGCAAGGAGCACUACCUGUCGGGGGCCCAGGAGCCCGACUCCAUGGCUGGUGUCAUUGUGGAGCAGGGCCAGGGGCCCAGCAAGCUGUUUGUGGGCACUGCUGUCGACGGCAAGUCGGAGUACUUCCCCACCUUGAGCUCCCGCAAGCUCAUCAGUGAUGAAGACAGCGCGGACAUGUUCAGUCUCGUGUACCAGGAUGAGUUUGUGUCCUCCCAGAUCAAGAUCCCCUCAGACACGCUGUCCUUGUACCCUGCCUUUGACAUCUACUACAUCUACGGCUUCGUCAGCGCCUCCUUCGUGUACUUCCUGACGCUGCAGCUGGACACCCAGCAGACGCUGUUGGACACAGCGGGCGAGAAAUUUUUCACGUCCAAGAUCGUGCGCAUGUGCGCGGGAGACUCAGAGUUCUACUCAUACGUGGAAUUCCCCAUCGGCUGCUCCUGGCGCGGCGUGGAGUACCGCUUGGUGCAGAGCGCCCACCUGGCCAAGCCUGGCCUGCUGCUGGCCCAGGCCCUGGGCGUGCCGGCUGAUGAGGACGUCCUCUUCACCAUCUUCUCUCAGGGCCAGAAGAACCGGGCCAGCCCACCCCGGCAGACCAUCCUCUGCCUCUUCACCCUCAGCAACAUCAAUGCCCACAUCCGGCGCCGCAUCCAGUCCUGCUAUCGUGGGGAGGGCACUCUGGCUCUGCCCUGGCUGCUGAACAAGGAGCUGCCCUGCAUCAACACCCCCAUGCAGAUCAACGGCAACUUCUGUGGGCUGGUGUUGAACCAGCCUCUGGGAGGCCUGCAUGUGAUCGAGGGGCUGCCCCUGCUGGCCGACAGCACCGACGGCAUGGCCAGCGUGGCCGCCUACACCUACCGCCAGCACUCUGUGGUCUUCAUUGGCACGCGCAGCGGCAGCUUGAAGAAGGUGCGGGUCGAUGGCUUCCAGGAUGCCCACCUGUAUGAGACAGUCCCCGUGGUGGAUGGCAGCCCCAUCCUCCGAGACCUGCUCUUCAGCCCGGACCACCGGCACAUCUAUCUCCUGAGUGAGAAGCAGGUGAGCCAGCUCCCGGUGGAGACCUGUGAGCAGUACCAGAGCUGCGCAGCCUGCCUGGGCUCCGGGGACCCGCACUGUGGUUGGUGUGUGCUGCGACACAGGUGCUGCCGCGAAGGGGCCUGUCUGGGCGCCUCUGCCCCACACGGCUUUGCUGAGGAGCUGAGCAAGUGUGUCCAGGUGCGGGUCCGGCCCAACAAUGUGUCAGUGACGUCACCUGGGGUGCAGCUGACCGUCACCCUGCACAACGUGCCAGACCUCAGUGCGGGCGUGAGCUGCGCCUUCGAGGCGGCGGCGGAGAACGAGGCGGUCCUGCUGCCCUCCGGUGAACUGCUCUGCCCCUCACCCUCCCUCCAGGAGCUCCGAGCUCUUACCAGGGGGCAUGGGGCCACCCGCACUGUGCGGCUGCAGCUUCUCUCCAAGGAGACAGGCGUGAGGUUUGCCGGUGCUGACUUUGUCUUCUACAACUGCAGCGUCCUCCAGUCGUGCAUGUCCUGUGUUGGCAGCCCUUACCCCUGCCACUGGUGUAAGUACCGCCACACGUGUACCAGCCGCCCCCACGAGUGCUCCUUCCAGGAGGGCAGGGUCCACAGCCCUGAGGGCUGCCCUGAGAUCCUGCCCAGUGGGGACCUCCUGAUCCCCGUUGGGGUCAUGCAGCCUCUUACCUUGCGGGCUAAGAACCUACCUCAGCCGCAGUCGGGCCAGAAGAACUAUGAGUGCGUGGUGCGGGUGCAGGGGCGGCAGCAGCGGGUGCCUGCCGUGCGCUUCAACAGCAGCAGUGUGCAGUGCCAGAACGCCUCGUACUCCUAUGAAGGUGAUGAGCAUGGUGACACCGAGCUGGACUUUUCCGUGGUCUGGGAUGGAGACUUCCCCAUAGACAAGCCUCCCAGCUUCCGAGCCCUCCUGUACAAGUGCUGGGCGCAGCGGCCCAGCUGUGGCCUCUGCCUCAAGGCUGAUCCCCGCUUCAACUGUGGCUGGUGCAUCUCAGAGCACAGGUGCCAGCUGCGGACCCACUGCCCGGCCCCGAAGACCAACUGGAUGCACCUGAGCCAGAAGGGCACCCGGUGCAGCCACCCCCGCAUCACGCAGAUCCACCCUCUCGUGGGGCCCAAGGAAGGAGGCACCCGGGUCACCAUCGUGGGUGAGAACCUGGGCCUCUUGUCCCGAGAGGUGGGCCUGCGGGUGGCUGGCGUGCGUUGCAACUCCAUUCCGGCCGAGUACAUCAGUGCUGAGAGGAUCGUGUGUGAGAUGGAGGAGUCGCUGGUGCCCAGCCCGCCGCCGGGGCCCGUGGAGCUGUGUGUGGGUGACUGUUCAGCCGACUUCCGCACGCAGUCGGAGCAGGUCUACAGCUUUGUGACCCCAACGUUUGACCAAGUGAGUCCCAGCCGUGGCCCGGCGUCCGGGGGCACACGGCUUACCAUCUCAGGCAGCUCUCUGGAUGCUGGCAGCAGGGUCACAGUGACUGUGAGGGACAGCGAGUGCCAGUUUGUAAGGAGAGAUGCCAAGGCGAUCGUGUGCAUCUCACCUCUCUCCACCCUGGGCCCCAGCCAGGCCCCCAUCACACUUGCCAUUGACCGGGCUAACAUCUCCAGCCCCGGGCUCAUCUACACCUACACUCAGGACCCCACCGUCACCCGCCUUGAGCCCACCUGGAGCAUCAUCAAUGGAAGCACUGCCAUCACUGUGAGUGGGACCCACCUGCUGACGGUCCAGGAGCCCCGGGUCCGUGCCAAGUACCGCGGCAUUGAGACCACCAAUACAUGCCAAGUGAUCAACGACACUGCCAUGCUGUGUAAGGCCCCCGGCAUCUUUCUUGGGCGGCCCCAGCCUCGGGCGCAAGGCGAGCACCCUGAUGAGUUUGGCUUCCUGCUGGACCACGUGCAAACGGCCCGCUCCCUCAACCGCUCCUCCUUUACCUACUACCCUGAUCCCAGCUUUGAGCCGCUGGGGCCCUCUGGCGUGCUGGACGUCAAACCGGGCUCCCACGUGGUGCUGAAGGGCAAGAACCUGAUUCCCGCUGCAGCCGGCAGCUCCCGCCUCAACUACACUGUGCUGAUAGGAGGCCAGCCGUGUUCGCUCACUGUCUCGGACACACAACUCCUGUGCGACUCACCCAGCCAGACUGGCCGGCAGCCUGUCAUGGUGCUGGUGGGUGGCCUGGAGUUCUGGCUGGGCACCCUGCACAUCUCGGCAGAGCGGGCGCUGACCCUACCGGCCAUGAUGGGGCUGGCGGCGGGGGGUGGGCUCCUGCUGCUGGCCAUCACAGCCGUGCUGGUGGCCUACAAGCGCAAGACUCAGGACGCGGACCGUACCCUCAAGCGUCUGCAGCUGCAGAUGGACAACCUGGAGUCCCGUGUGGCCCUGGAGUGCAAGGAAGCUUUUGCAGAGCUGCAGACGGACAUCAAUGAGCUGACUAACCACAUGGACGAGGUGCAGAUCCCCUUCCUGGACUACCGGACUUACGCCGUGCGCGUGCUCUUCCCGGGCAUCGAGGCCCACCCGGUGCUCAAGGAGCUGGAUACGCCACCCAACGUGGAGAAGGCCCUGCGCCUCUUCGGGCAGCUGCUGCACAGCCGCGCGUUCGUGCUUACCUUCAUCCACACGCUGGAGGCCCAGAGCAGCUUCUCCAUGCGCGACCGCGGCACCGUGGCCUCGCUCACCAUGGUGGCCCUGCAGAGCCGGCUCGACUAUGCCACGGGGCUGCUCAAGCAACUGCUGGCCGACCUCAUCGAGAAGAACCUCGAGAGCAAGAACCACCCCAAGCUGCUGCUACGCAGGACAGAGUCAGUGGCUGAGAAGAUGCUUACCAACUGGUUCACGUUCCUGCUGCAUAAGUUUCUGAAGGAGUGUGCUGGGGAGCCUCUCUUCCUGCUUUACUGUGCCAUCAAGCAGCAGAUGGAGAAGGGCCCCAUUGAUGCCAUCACGGGCGAGGCACGAUACUCCCUGAGCGAGGACAAGCUCAUCCGUCAGCAGAUCGACUACAAGACACUGACCCUUCACUGCGUGUGUCCGGAGAACGAGGGCAGCGCCCAGGUCCCAGUGAAGGUUCUCAACUGUGACAGCAUCACCCAGGCCAAAGAUAAGCUGCUGGACACUGUGUACAAGGGCAUUCCGUACUCCCAGCGUCCCAAAGCUGAGGACAUGGACCUGGAGUGGCGCCAGGGCCGCAUGACUCGCAUCAUCCUCCAGGAUGAGGAUGUCACCACCAAGAUCGAGUGUGACUGGAAGAGGCUCAACUCACUGGCCCACUACCAGGUGACAGACGGUUCCUUGGUGGCAUUGGUGCCCAAACAAGUGUCUGCCUAUAACAUGGCCAACUCCUUCACCUUCACCCGCUCCCUCAGCCGCUACGAGAGCUUGCUCCGCACGGCCAGCAGCCCUGAUAGCCUCCGCUCACGGGCACCCAUGAUUACGCCUGACCAGGAGACAGGCACCAAAUUGUGGCACCUGGUGAAAAACCACGACCAUGCCGACCAUCGCGAGGGGGACCGUGGCAGCAAGAUGGUCUCCGAGAUCUACCUGACACGGCUGCUGGCCACCAAGGGCACACUGCAGAAGUUCGUGGAUGACCUCUUUGAGACAGUGUUCAGCACAGCCCACCGGGGCUCGGCCCUGCCCCUGGCCAUCAAGUACAUGUUCGACUUCCUGGAUGAGCAGGCGGACCAGCGCCAGAUCAGCGACCCCGAUGUGCGCCACACCUGGAAGAGCAACUGCCUGCCGCUGCGCUUCUGGGUGAAUGUGAUCAAGAACCCGCAGUUCGUGUUCGACAUCCACAAGAACAGCAUCACGGAUGCCUGCCUGUCGGUGGUAGCCCAGACCUUCAUGGACUCCUGCUCUACAUCCGAGCACCGCCUGGGGAAGGACUCGCCCUCCAACAAACUGCUCUACGCCAAGGACAUCCCCAACUACAAGAGCUGGGUGGAGAGGUAUUAUCGAGACAUUGCAAAGAUGGCAUCCAUCAGCGACCAGGACAUGGAUGCCUACCUGGUGGAGCAGUCCCGCCUCCACGCCAGCGACUUCAGCGUCCUGAGUGCGCUCAACGAGCUGUAUUUCUAUGUCACCAAGUACCGCCAGGAGAUUCUCACGGCUCUGGACCGAGAUGCCUCUUGUCGGAAGCAUAAGUUGCGGCAGAAACUGGAACAGAUCAUCAGCCUCGUGUCCAGCGACAGCUAAGGUGGUGGAAUCGGUGAGGAGGGGGCUUCUCAGUCCUGUGCCGUCCUCCCAUCCAGGGGAGUGGCUGGCUCAAGCCUGGGUCCCCGGGCUGAGCCCUGGAUUGGGUAUCGUGGGGCAGGUCACCCUGGCCACGAUGCCCCCGGCACACCCAGGCCCCCUUCAUUAGUGCCUUGCUUUGGGCCCUGCAGGGGGAGGGGUGACAGGGCGAGCCCCCACCCCAGCAGCAGCAAUACCCCCACCCUCCUGCCCUGUGCCCAGGUGUUGGGACAGUCCCACCCUCCCUGCUAUUUAUAUCCCUCUGCCUAUUUAUUGAAUCGAACUUCGCCUCUGUCUCCAUCUGUAAAUAUGUGUCCCCCCACCGGAUGUCGCCACCCUCACUCACCUGCCUCUUCUUGAGCUGUCCUGGGCCCUGCCACCCGUCUGGGCUCCUUUGUGUAGCAUUAUCAGCCUCGGUCUGGCCUCUGGCACCUCACCCUUGCCAUGGCUGACCCCACCCAUUCCAAGGCGGGGUCACGGUACCAGCAGCACUUGGGGUGAGGCCUCCAAAGCUUCCUCAGAAUUGUGGCUGUGCCACGCUGGACCACAGGGUCCCCCUCAAGCAUCUCGGGGCCCUAUUCUCUCUGAGCACCUGGAGGGCUGGACUCAGGCUUGUGCCAGGGCCUGACUUGGGCCUGGGGGCCCUAGAACGCUCCUCCUCCUGAGCCUACUGCCAAACGUCCUCAGUGUUGUCUGCACCUGCUCCGACUCCUUCAGCCGCCCCAUUCAGCGCCCGCUCCGUCCAGUGCCCGCCCUGUGGGGCCAAGGCGGCCGUGCCUUACUACUCUGUGUCUUCUGCCUCCUCUGAGGAAUCUGGCCCUGUCUGACAGUCCCAGACCCCCCGUUCUCUCCUCUUUAGUUGCAUGAGUUUUUCUUUGUUCAUGGAAUGUUUUUUCCUGAUUAAAUGUUGGGGAAAUGCCAUCCAUGUGGGGCUCUGUCCUUGGGGCAGGUCAGUAGACCUGUGGAUGCUGCAUGAGCUGGAGCCCCAUUGUGGGAGAAAGGACCACUCCUUGCAGGGUCCCAGAGGGUUUGGGGAGGUUCAGGGCCAUACCCGACCCAUCAGCAAACCCCGGUGGCUCUACCUUCAAGACAGAUUCAAGGUAGAUAGAUUCUCCUCCCUUCCACCACCCCCACCCAGCUCUCCUGUGCCAUCGUCUAUCUCUGCCUGGAUGCCAGUCUCCCUGCUUCUGCCCUGGCUCUCUUCAGCCUGUUCUCAGCGUGGGAGGCAGAGAGAUCCUGUUAUGAUAUAAGGUGGAUCAUGUUGCCUCACUGUUUAGAACCCUCCGGCGGUUUCAGCUGCAGCCAGCUCCUUCAAAACCUGACAAUUGCAUACUGUCGAGGUUGUGGCACCCAUCAUGGUGCACCUACCAAAGUCUUACUCCCAGGCCUGUUAAGUAAUGCAGGUGGGGAGAAGGUGACAUGCAAUUUAUUUAUUUAUUUAUUUUGAGACAGAGUGUAGCUGUGUUGCCCAGGCUGGAGUGCAGUGGCAAGAUCACAGCUCAGUGCAGUCUCAAACUCCUGGGCUCAAGUGAUCCUCCCACCUCAGCCUCCUGAAUAGCUGGGUGUAUUAGUGCACUCUACUAUGCCAGGCUUUUUUUUUUUUUUUUUUUGAGAUAGGUUGCCGCUAUGUUGUUCAGGCUGGUCUUGAAUUCCUGGUCUCAAGUGAUCCUCACCCCUCAGCCUCCCAAAGUAUUGGGAUUACAGGCAUGAGCCACUGUGCCCGGCCAGGUGAGAUGGAAUCUUAUUUUUACUUUUUAUGUUUUUUUUUUUUUCUUUGACGGAGUGUCGCUCUGUCGCCCAGGCUGGAGUGCAGUGGCAUGAUCUCGGCUCACUGCAAGCUCCGCCUCCCAGGUUCACGCCAUUCUCCUGCCUCAGCCUCCCGAAUAGCUGGAACUACAGGUGCCCACCACCACGCCCGGCUAAUUUUUUGUAUUUUUAGUAGAGACGGGGUUUUACUGUGUUAGCCAGGAUGGUCUCGAUCUCCUGACCUCGUGAUCCACCUGCCUCAGCCUCCCAAAGUGCUGGGAUUACAGGCGUGAGCCACCAUGCCUGACCUUUUUUUUUUUUUUUUUUUUUUUUUUUUUUGGAGACGGGAUCUUGCCCUGUUGCCCACGCUGGAGUGCAGUGGCAAAAUCAACUCACUGCAGCCUUGAUGUCCUGGGCUCAAGUGAUCUUCCUGCCUCAGCCUUCUGAGUAGCUAGGAUUACAAGUGCUUGCCACCAUACCCAGCUGUUUUUUGUUUUUUUUUUUUUUCUUUAGUAGAGAUGGAGUCUUGCUGGUUUUGAACCUCCUGGGCUCAAGUGAUCCUCCUGUUUUGGCCUCCCAAAAUUCUGGGAUUACAGUUGUGAGCCACUGUGCCCAGCCAAGUGAGAUGCAAUUUUUUUUUUUUUUUUUUUUGAGACAGAGUUUCACUCUUGUUGCCCAGGCUGGAGUGCAAUGGUAUGAUCUUGGCUCACCGCAACCUCCGCCUCCCGGGUUCAAGUGAUUCUCCUGCCUCAGCCUCCUGAGUAGCUGAGAUUACAGGCAUGUGCCACCACGCCCAGCUAAUUUUGUAUUUUUAGUAGACACAGGGUUUCUCCAUGUUGGUCAGGCUGGUCUCGAGCUCCCGACCUCAGGUGAUCCGCCCGCCUCAGCCUCCCAAAGUGCUGGGAUUACAGGCAUGAGCCACUGUUCCUGGCCUUUCUUCUUUUUUUGUUUUUGUUUUUUUUUGAGAUGCAAUUUUAAAUAGGGUGGCUUGGACAGCCACCUGAGUUGGGUUUAAAAGCUGCCAGCUCCAGCCGUCCAGCUGUGGGGCCACGGUGCCAGACAGUGGUGGUGGUUAUAGGACCGUAGGUGUUUACCAAAACUAGACAAGUCCACAUAACAACCAACUGCACAAAUAAGGAGUAAAAUAAUAAAGAGAAGGACGUGUGAGGCAGGACUGGAUUGUAGCCCAGGAUAAAGAGAAGUUGCGGGAUGACAGCUGUGCCGUCGGCCCAGACAGAACCAUCUGGACAGAGGACAGAGGAUAAGGGAGAUGGUUGAAAAUACUACCAUCAUAUGAUAAUGACAACUAAGCCACAGGAAAACAAGGCAGUUUUAACCUCAGGGGAAAUCCCUCAGAAAUGGAUGGAAUCUACCAGAAGCAUCAUGAGAGGAAGAGGAAGGGAAACAGAGCUAAAUUGGGGCCAGGUGUGGUGGCUCGCACUUGUCAUCCCAGCACUUUUGGAGGCCCAGGCGGGAAGAUCACUGGAGCCCAGGAGUUCAGGACCAGCCUGGGCAACAAAGCGAGAUCCCCUCUCUACAAAAAAUAAAAAACUAGCCAGGCAUGGUGGUGCAUGCCUGUGGUCCCAGUUACUCAGGAGGCUGAGGUGCUGGGGAACAAGGCUGCAGUGAGCUGUGAUUGUGCCAGCCUAGGUGACAGAGCCAGACCCUGUAUCAAAAAAAAUAAUAAUAAUUAAAAAACAAAAGAUCGGCUGGGCGCGGUGGCUCAUGCCUGUAAUCCCAGCACUUUGGGAGGCUGAGGUGGGUGGACCACCUGAGGUCGGGAGUUCGAGACCAGCCUCACCAACAUGGAGAAACCCUGUGUCUACUAAAAAUACAAAAUUAGCUGGGCGUGGUGGUGCAUGCCUGUAAUUCUAGCUACUUGGGAGGCUGAGGCAGGAGAAUUCACUUGAACCCGGGAAGUGGAGGUUGCGGUGAGCCAAGAUCGCACCAUUGCACUCCAGCCUGGGCAACAAGAGUGAAACACUGUCUCAAAAAAAAAAAAAAAAAGUGAAAGAUCUAAAUUGUCAACUAUUCGUCAAUAAUUAAUGUCUAAAAAAUAUUAAGAAAGGAAGAAAGGAAUGAGAGCAAAAGAGAGGGAGAGAGGAAAGUGUCAUCUUCAUAAGCUGAAGGCCAGUGCCACCGUCACCACUGGCAGAGCUCCCCAGAUUCUACAAAGGGAAACUGUUCCUCCAUAUGGAGUAAUAGGGACUGGAUAUGUCAUGCCAAAUGAAAGAACACGCCAAACCAGACAAAAUAUAUGGAAUGCAGAGUAUUAAAAAACUGGCUGUGGGCCAGUGAGGGACAGCGACGUGUGGGAGCUGGGAAACAAGGUAAGCCAUGCGACUGGCCCAGUGUCCUGUGUGGAGUUUCCUGGUGGAGCCUGGCAGACACCCGGACUUUAGGAGUUGAAACUGAUUCAGAGCGUCCCAGCAGCUGGAGUUUGCAGGGCGGAGAACCAGAGAGAAGAGAGCUGCACAGGGAAAGAACCCUGGAUAUCCACAGAGGCUCCCGUUCCAGUGUGCAGCGGACUACGACUACUGGUGAGCACAGGCGUGUGAGGAAGCUACCCAAGACCAGGGAAGGCCAUCACCCCAGCAGGAGAGGAUGAACGGUAACUCCAGUGUGCAAGCAGGACAGGGACUAGCAGCUGUCCCCACCCACCAGGAUAGAGAAGCUCAUGUUCACCUAGGCAGCACUGGCCAGGGUGCCCAGAAUGGUGUUUGUUGCCUCCAUAGAGGGAAACAAGCCUACAGUUAAGAGCUGCUCUGGUCCCACACAGCACAUCUUCAAAGCAAGACUCAAAAGGAUCAAACCAUUUCCUUGUUUUCUGAGAAUAAAAGCAGUUGUACCUCUUCCUUUUCACUCUCAGAAAAUCUGAUAGAAUCUAUAAAAGAGCCCUAAGGCUGGAGACACUGUAUUUUCCAGGGAGCCAACUCCUUGCCCCAGACACUAGUCAAUUGCCCCAGCACUUUCUUCACUGAUCGUUAGAGGAAAAAAGCUCAUGUUAGAUUUAAAAAUCAGGAAAAAAAUUUAACACUAAACUUGCAAAUAUUAUGUGGUGUAUAUUACAGUUACACAUUUACUAUGUAAGUGCAACUGUAAAACUGAGGAAGUAUUCCAAAAUGUUGACAGUAGUUAAUCCUGAAUGACAGAACCCAAUUGAUUUUCAUUUUCUUCCAUUUCCUAAAUUGUCUUCAAUUUCCUUGUACUCCUUGAAUAUCUGAAUUCUAGAACCCCCCCCCCAGCAACCCAAGCACAACAAGAAUAUUGGGAGGUGCCCCAGCUGCAAAUAAACUCAGACUUGGAAUAGUA